GGAGCUUUCUACACCCCUCUGAGCUCCCGCUCCUGGCUCUGUAGCUGAGAGAAGCCCUGGCAGGUCAGUGGCAGGCACUGUCACGCUGAGUCCUAUGCUGGCAGCGGGGAACCUUGGGGAGAACACGGGACACCGCGGAAGCCGGGAAAUGAUUGUGCGGCUGUAACCGGCACAGGUUCGCGGUCCGAGUCACUGCACCGAGACUCCAAGGCCUGCAGCAGAAACAGUUUAAUAGGGGGAGAGGAGAGAAGACCCCAGUUCCGCCUCCAUGAGAGGUUUGGGGAUGGGGGUGUUUAGGGGUCUGGACAGGGGCGGCUGAAGUGUGGGGUCGCUGGUUGGUGGGGAAGUGACAGGCGAAUCCUGGGACGGGAGGUGAAGAAACCGCAUUCUCCUGCUGAGUGGGUUCCCUCGUGGGGUUUUCACCCUGCUUGGCGCCAGCCUUUCCGUUGGAAUUCAAGAUCUGAGAAAGAACUUGGGCAACUCGAGCAGCUCUCCGAGAUCUUAUCCCCAGGCACAAUGCAGAAGCCGGCGGUCAGUGUCUUCUGUGACCUGACUCUCAGGAAGGCGGCCCCCGCGAGGCAGUGGGGCUCAGGUUUCCAUUCCUUGGGGACACACGGCUGGUCAGCCAGUUGAAUGAUUGUAUUUGGGGGAGAAGACAGAAGUGAUCUCUUCCUUCCUGACUCUCAGACUAAUGAAGAGAGAAAACAAUAUGAUUCAGUAGCCUUUGAGGAUGUGGCGGUGAACUUCACCCAGGAAGAGUGGGCUUUGCUGGGUCCAUCACAGAAGAGUCUGUACAGAGAUGUGAUGUGGGAAACCAUUAGGAACCUGGACUGUAUAGGAAUGAAAUGGGAAGACACAAACAUUGAAGAUCAGCACAGAAAUCCCAGGAGGAGCCUAAGAUGUCAUAUCAUAGAGAGAUUUAGUGAAAGUCGCCAGCCAGAUAGUACUGUGAAUGAAAAACCUCCUGGAGUAGAUCCAUGUAAAAGCAGUGUGUGUGGAGAAAUCAUGGGUUGUUCAUUCCUUAAUUGCUAUAUCACAUUUGAUGCUGGACACAAACCAGAUGAGUGUCAGGAAUAUGGAGAGAAGCCACAUACACAUAAACAAUGUGGGACAGCCUUCAAUUAUCACCACUCCUUUCAAACACAGGAAAGACCUCACACUGGAAAGAAACGCUAUGAUUGUAAGGAAUGUGGGAAAACCUUCAGUUCUUCGGGAAACCUUCGAAGACACAUAAUAGUACAACGUGGAGGUGGACCUUAUAUAUGUAAGUUGUGUGGGAAAGCCUUUUUUUGGCCUAGUUUAUUUCGUAUGCAUGAAAGAACUCACACUGGAGAGAAACCGUAUGAAUGUAAGCAGUGUUGUAAAGCCUUCCCUAUUUACAGUUCCUAUCUAAGACAUGAAAGAACACACACUGGGGAGAAACCAUAUGAAUGCAAGCACUGUUCCAAAGCCUUCCCUGAUUACAGUUCCUAUGUAAGACAUGAAAGAACUCACACUGGAGAAAAACCCUAUAAAUGUAAACGAUGUGGAAGAGCCUUCAGUGUUUCCAGUUCCCUUCGAAUACAUGAAAGAACUCACACUGGAGAGAAACCCUAUGAAUGCAAGCAAUGCGGGAAAGCAUUUCAUCAUCUGGGAAGCUUUCAAAGACACAUGAUAAGGCACACUGGAGAUGGACCUCAUAAAUGUAAGAUAUGUGGGAAAGGCUUUGAUUGUCCUAGUUCACUGCAAAGUCAUGAAAGAACUCACACUGGAGAGAAACCCUAUGAAUGCAAGCAGUGUGGGAAAGCGUUAUCUCAUCACUCAAGCUUUCGAAGUCAUAUGAUAAUGCACACUGGAGAUGGACCUCACAAAUGCAAGGUAUGUGGGAAAGCCUUCAUUUAUCCCAGUGUAUUUCAAGGACAUGAAAGGACUCAUACUGGUGAGAAACCCUAUGAAUGUAAAGAAUGUGGUAAAGCCUUCCGUAUUUCUAGUUCCCUUCGAAGACAUGAAACAACUCACACUGGAGAGAAACCCUAUAAAUGUAAAUGUGGGAAAGCCUUUAUUGAUUUCUAUUCCUUUCAAAAUCAUGAAACAACUCACACUGGAGAGAAGCCAUAUGAGUGUAAGGAAUGUGGGAAAGCAUUCAGUUGUUUCACAUACCUUUCUCAACAUAGAAGGACUCACAUGGCUGAAAAACCUUAUGAAUGUAAAACAUGUAAGAAAGCCUUCAGUCAUUUUGGUAACUUAAAAGUCCAUGAAAGGAUUCACACUGGAGAGAAGCCAUAUGAAUGUAAGGAAUGCAGGAAAGCAUUCUCUUGGCUCACUUGCCUUCUGCGACAUGAAAGAAUUCACACUGGAAAGAAAUCUUAUGAAUGUCAACAAUGUGGUAAAGCCUUCACUCGUUCUCGUUUCCUUCGAGGACAUGAAAAAACUCACACUGGAGAGAAGAUGCAUGAAUGUAAGGAAUGUGGGAAGGCACUGAGUUCUCUCAGUUCCUUGCAUAGACAUAAAAGGACUCACUGGAGAGAUACUCUAUAAAUGUGGAAAAGCAUUCAUUAAUUUUAUUUCAUUUCAGAAACGUGAAAGAAAUCACAUAGGAGAUAAGCCUCAUGAAUGCAAACACAUGGUAAAGCCUUAAGAUGUUUCUUUUGAAUAUGGUUAUCCCCUAACCAUAUGCAGGGGAUUGGUUCCAGACCCCCUAAGCAUACCUAAAUCCACAGAUGCUGUGUUCCUUUUAUAAAAGGACAUUUGCAUGUAACCUAUCCACAUCCUCCUGCAUCCCAUAAAUCAUGCCUAGAUUACUUAAUUUUUCACCAACCCAAAGCUUUUGUAAAAGUAAAAAUAAAAAGUAGGUUACUAAAAUACCUCAUGUGUUGUAAAAGCUAUGUAAACAGUCAUUUUAUUGUAUUUUUUUUAGAGAAUCGUGAUAUGAAAAUAAUCCUGUGCUGUUGAGAACAGACCCAACCAUCACAGGCCUGCCUACAUAGUACAUGUCACCUAGAAUGUUACAGUUUCUUUUUUUCUUUUUUUUUUUUUUAAGACAGAGUUUCACUCUUAUUGCCCAGGCUGGAGGGCAAUGGCACAAUCUCAGCUCACUGCAUCCUCUGCCUCCCGGGUUCAAGCAAUUCUCCUGUCUUAGCCUCCUGAGUAGCUGGGAUUACAGAUGCAUGCCACCACACCCAGCUAAUUUUUUUUUUUUUUUUUUUUUUUUUGUAUUUUUAGUAGAGACGGGGUUUCAUCAUAUUGGUCAGGCUGGUCUCGAACUCCUGACCUCAGAUGAUCUGCCUGCCUUGGUCUCCCAAAGUGCUGGGAUUACAGGCAUGAGCCUGUAAUCUACAGUUUCUUUUUUUUCAACAAUCAUAGAUUGCUUUUAUUUAAUGACCUGGAAUCGUGUGUUAACACUUAUGAAAAUCCUGAUCCUUCUUGCUUGAUAACCCAAGGAUGAUGAUGAUGAUCAUGAUCAUGAUGAUGCUGAUUACAGUAUGGUGCCUAAUAUGAUUCACUGAGGUGACUAGAUGGGUGGCACUGUAGAUAAACAGUGAGACAUCAGGCUCACUUGAAUCUUGACAGGAUGUCAGGAUGAUCAUCUGUGUUGGAUGAACCAGGUUCUGAUUGCAGAUGCUGAGUUUGGAAGAGACUAAAUAAUACUAAUGUCAGAAUCUGUUCAGCAUGAGGGCUGAAGAUGUGUACACACUGAAGGAUCUGUCUUCAUAUUUGCAGAUAUUUAGUUAGAAACAUUGUUGUAGGAAGCUGGUUCUUUUUCUUUAAAUAUCCUUGCAGUGUUUGUUGGCAUGUUAUCCCUUGGGUGACACAGAGGUUUUGUUCCAUUGAAGGAUCUUACUUGAGGAUGGCAAUCUUUAUUUUAUUUUUAUUUUUAUUUAUUUAUUUAUCAUUUGAGACUGAGUUUCGUUCUUAUUGCCCAGUCUGGAGUGCAGUGGCGCGAUCUCGACUCACUGCAACCUCCACCUCCCAGAUUCAAGCGAUUCUCCUGCCUCAGCCUCCAGAGUAGCUGGGAUUACAGGCACUCGCCACCAUGCCUGGCUAAUUUUUAUUUUUAGUAGAGAUGGGGUUUCACCAUGUUGGUCAGGCUGGUCUCGAACUCCUGACCUCAGGUGAUCCACCUGCCUCGGCCUCCCAAAGUGCUGAGAUUACAGGCAUGAGCCACCGUGCCCUGCGAGGAUUGUAAUCUUUAAUACUUUUCACCUUGCAGAGGCUGUAGAUGCCCCAAAAACUGCUGCACAUGUUUCAAGUGUCACAUCUUUGAUAUUACCUCUUCUAAGUCUUCUGCAUCAUCAUUAUCAUCAUUAUCUGCAGAGAAUUUCAGUAUAUCUUCGAGUUCCUUGUUAGUAUUUAUGCUCUCUUAUUUGUGUUGGGAUAGAAAGAUUAAGGAAAGGAGAGAUGAGAAGGUGGCUCAACAGUUGAGACAGUUUUAUUGGGAGUAAACCUGAGAAGGGCUUCCAGCGGCAGGGUCAGGUGCAAACUUCUCUUACAGCCUGAGGCUUUUUUAAAGGGCCCAGUGGAGAAGUGUGCUUUGAAACAAAAUUCUGUUAGGGAGGGGUUGGGGAAGUCCUGGCUGUUCUGUUACAGUUAGGGCCGUUAUUCUCUGUUGAAGUUAUGGGCGGGGCUGACAUUUUCAGUUUUGGCCAGGUGGCCAAAUAGAAACUUAAAGCUUAGGAUGGUGGAGUGUUAUAAAGAUGGCGGUGCUCUUGUCCUGUCAAUGUGUUCCUCAAUAAAGUCUUCAAGCAUGUCAUAGAUUGUUUUCCCCACCAACCUCCCUUGCAGCAUUUGAGAUAUUCCUGAUACUUCAUCAAUAGUGGAGAAGCUCCUGAAAUCAUUGACUUCCUCACUCCAUAAUGGUUUCCAACACCCAAUGAAGUAGUAGGAGGAAAACAUGGGUUUCUUCUCCUGGAAGCCUCCAGAAGAAGGUAUUUCAAUAUGGGGAGAGUGGUCAGCUGUGUCACAGGUCACUGAGAAUUUGAAUAAGACAAGGAAAAAGGGUUGACUGUAGAUUUUGGCAAGUAUUUGGUCACUGGGGGCCUUGAUAAGAGCUGUUUCAUUGAAGUAUUCAUGAGAAUAACUUGUAGUGAAAUAUAUCUCAAAUAGACCUCCACGAUGUUGCCUAGAGGGCAGUGUUACCCUUUGAACUACCAACAUUAACCACUGGAACUGCUCAUCUGGAAGCCUCUUACAGUGCUGGUACAAACUAGAAUACACAAAGGAAGGGAUCAUUUUAUACGUGUUACUGUGCUACUUGCUCUAUCUACUUAGUGUUCCAUACAUGUAAUUACCUAUUCCAUCCUAUCCCAAAGUACUGAAAAUCUCCAUUCUACUUUCUCUGUCUGUGAAUUUGACUAUUCAUAGAGAGAGAGAUAUGUGGAAGUAUGCAUGUGUCCUUCCAUGUCUGGCUUAUUUCACUUAGAACGUUUUCAAGGUUUAUCCAUGUGGUAGCAUGUAUCAGGAACUCAUUGUUUUUGUGUCUGAAUAAAUUUCCACUGUAUGGUUAAAGCAUACUUUGUUUAUCCAUUUUUAUGUUGAUAAACAUGGGUUGUUUCCACAGUAAUAAUUUGACUGCUAUCAAUAAGGCUGCUGUGGAUGUGGUAUGUCUAUGUCUGUGUGAGUCCCUGCUUUCAAUUCUUUUGGAUAUAUGUAUCCCUAGGAGUGUAAUUGCUGGUUCACAGAAUAAUUGGUGUAAACCUUUUUCAGGAACAGGUAUAUUGCUUUACAAAGUGGCUACAAUGUUUUACAUUCUCUCCAGCAAUGCAUAAGGGUUUCUAUUUUCCACAUUGUCACAUAUACUGGUUGUCGUAUUUUUUUCAUAAUAGCCAAUUAAUGGUUCUGUACUGCUUUUUCAUUGUGGUUUUGAUUUGCAUUUCCCUAAUGACCAAUAAUAAUGCACAUUGGUUUUUGUUUUUGUUGGUUGUUUAUAUAUUUUUUGAACCAGUUUGUUUUAAAAUCCUUUGCUCAUUAAAAUUGAGUCAUUUGUGUUUUGUUGUUGAGUUAUAGGAAUUCUUAUUUAAAAUUUUUAGUUUUUAAUAUUUAGAAAAUUUCUUUCUUUUUUCAGCUCCCAAGUGCUUGGAAGAGAGUUGUAGGAAUUCUUUAUACACUGUGGGUAUUAAGCCCUUAUUUGAUAUGUGAUAUGCAGAUGUGUUCUCCCUUUCUGUAGGUUUUCUUUUCAUCUUGAGAUUGUCCUUUGGUGCGCAAAAGUUUUUAAUUUCGAUGUAGUCCAGUUUAUCUUUUAUUGGUUGUCUGUGCCUUAAAUGUCGUAUCCAAUAAAUCACUGCCAAAUUUAACAAAA